GGCAACCCGUUGGGGUUGCCUUUCUGGACUGUGGGUGCUUUGUUCUUUGUAAUAAAUCUUGUUGCUUGCUAACCCUUUGGGUCCCUACUGUCUUUGUGAGCUAUAACACUCGCCGUGAAGAUCUGUAUUUGCAGCUCUUUCUUGAGGCCCGUGUGACCACGAACCCACCGAGAGCGAAGGAACAACUCCAGGUGUGCCCUCUUAAGAGAUUUAACACUCAUUGCGAAGAUCUGCAGCUUCACUCCUGAAGCUAGCGAGACCAUGAACCCGCCAGAAGGAAGAAACUCCAGACACGCAGUCUUUAAGAAUUGUAACACCGCGAUGGUCCGCGGUUUCAUUCUUGAAGUCAGUGAGACCAAGAAUCCACCAUUUCCGGACACAAUAUGAUAUCAGUCUGGUGGAAAGGACAGAGGACUAAGUCCAUGGACUGGAAAUUGGAAGGGAGUACUCAGAAAGUAGAGUCACCUGUGCUGCAGGGGCAAGAAGGCAUCCUAGAGGAGACAGGUGAAGAUGGACUUCCUGAAGGCUUCCAGCUUCUGCAGAUCGAUGCGGAAGGCGAGUGCCAGGAGGGAGAGAUCCUGGCCACAGGCAGUACGGCAUGGUGCUCGAAAAAUGUCCAGAGAAAACAGAGACACUGGGAAAAGAUAGUUGCAGCAAAGAAGAGCAAAAGAAAGCAAGAAAAAGAACGAAGAAAAGCCAAUCGUGCAGAAAAUCCAGGCAUUUGCCCCCAGCACAGCAAACGUUUCCUGAGAGCUCUAACCAAAGACAAACUUUUGGAAGCCAAACACUCAGGACCAAGACUAUGUAUCGAUUUGAGUAUGACCCACUACAUGUCAAAGAAGGAAUUAAGUAGACUGGCUGGACAGAUUCGAAGGUUGUAUGGUUCAAACAAAAAAGCUGACAGGCCAUUUUGGAUCUGCCUCACUGGAUUCACAACAGACAGUCCCCUUUAUGAAGAGUGUGUGAGGAUGAAUGAUGGAUUUUCUAGUUACCUGUUAGACAUAACAGAAGAAGACUGCUUUAGUUUAUUUCCCUUGGAAACCCUUGUGUACCUGACUCCUGACUCAGAACACGCUCUUGAAGAUGUUGAUCUAAACAAAGUUUACAUCCUCGGUGGGCUUGUGGAUGAAAGCAUUCAGAAGAGACGAAGUCUCUUGAUGUUGCUCAGGCUGGUCUUGAACUCCAGGCCUCAAGCAAUCCUUCUGCCUCAGCCUCCCAAAACACUGGGAUUACAGGCAUGAACCACCCUGUCCAGCCCAAAAUAUGUAUUUAUAUACAGAGAGAAAAAGCAACAUAUUAACAACUGGUGAGUCUAGAUUACAGGAAUGAAUAUUGAUUGUAUUAUUUUGAACUUUUCUUAGGUUUGAAAUACUUCAAAGUAAAAAGUUAGGGUCGGGCGUGGUGGCUCACGCCUAUAAUCCCAGCCCUUUGGGAGGCCAAGUCAGGCAAAUCACAAGGUCAAGAGAUCGAUACCAUCCUGGCCAACAUGUGAAAACCCUGUCUCUACUAAAAACAUAAAAAUUAGCUGAGUGUGGUGGCAUGUGCCUGUAGUCCCAGCUACUCGGGAGGCUGAGGCAGGAGAAUCUCUUGAACCAGGGAGGCGGAGGUUGCAGUGAGCCGAAAUCACACCACUGUAGUCCAGCCUGGUGACAGAGCGAGACUCUGUUUCAUACACACACAAAGUCUGGAGGGCUGGAGGACUACUUGAACCCAAGAGUUAGAGGCUGCAGAGAACUGUGGUCACACCACUGCACUUCAGCCUGGGUGAUGCAACACAGUGAGACCCUGUCUCUAAAAAAAAAAAAAAAAAACAACAAUAAUAAUAAUUAAAAGUUUAUUAGUCUUACCUGCAGCAGGGUGACAGCGCCCCCACCCCGUCCAAGACAGGGCCUUGCUCUGCUGCCCAGGCUGGAGGGCAGUGGCACAAUCAGCUUACUCCAGGCUCAAUUGAUCCCCCUACCUCAGCUUCCCAAGUAGCUGGGACCACAGGUGGGCGCUACCAUGCCCAGCUAAUUUUUUGUUGAGUUGGGGUUUCACCGUAUGGCCCAUGCUGGUGUCGAACUGCUGGGCUGAAGUUACCCACCUGCCUCACCCUCCCAAAGUGCUGAGAUUGCAGGCAUGAGCCACGGUGCCUGGCCAACAGUCCCUUUUUUGAGGCAGUUAAGUUCAGAGGGUCAGUGAGCAGUGCAUGACUUACAGAUGUGCAGUUUUAACAUAUUAUCUGUCCACCAACAUUUAAACUGAAAAAUAACUGGAAGAUUUGUGAGAUGUUUAGAACUUUUUGGUUGUUAUUGGAGUUUGGCUUCUUCACAGAAAUAAGCUAAGAACAACAUUUCUUCAAGGAGAGUCAUUUUAUUAUGAAUCAUUGUGCAAAGAACAUAAACUAAAUUGUAAGCUCUUCUAGGGCAACACCCAAAUAUCCUAAUUUUGAAUUCUGUACUUCAAAGUGAUUAUAAAGGAAUAAGACUUUUUAUAAAACAAACGUAUCAUAUAGCUCAUAUAUGCAAAGGAGUUUUAUCCUUUCAAAUAAGUCCCUGUAUCGCUUAAAACAUUUUUGGAAGUUCUAUCUAAAAUUUUGUUUCAUGUGAGGCAGGUGUCAGCACCGAAAAGGUACUAGGUCCACUUCACACUAUUCCACCUGGUUAGACCAUACUCAUGAUGGCCAGUCAGUUAUGGGACCGUAAACAAAAUGAUACUGGACUAGCUUAGAACAAGUUCAACUUGUCCUGAAUGAUGAAGGGACUUGAAAUUCAAAGAAGAGUUGACAGAACUGAGGCUACAAUCUGGAGACUAGAGGAUUCCUAGGGGCAUGAUCACUGCCUUCAAGUUUCUGAAUGGCCAUCUUUUGGAAGGGCCAUCUUACUUGCAUGGUUUGGCCUUGGGGGAAUAGACCUAGGAUGAAUGAGUGGAAGUCUCAAAGAAAACAGAAUUUUGCUCAAGAUCAAGAAGAAUUUCCUAUCAGCUGGUACUAUCAAAACUGGAGUGGGUUGUCCCAGGAUGCAUGAACUCCCUGUCACAAGAGCUGUCCAUUGAGUGGCCACAUGGCCUCUUGGAGAAGUCAUAGAGAACAGACAAUGAAUGGGUGGUUAGAGUGAUACAGUUAACACUAUUGAGACCCCUUCCAAGCCUUGGCAUGUUAAUUAUCCCAGUAAUCUGAACCUUUCUCUUUAAUCCUGAAGUCUUAGGUAGAAAAUCUUUCCUGUGCUUCUUACAAGGCAGCAAAUGUAAUCUGACUGAGUCAUGACUCAGUCUGAGGGACUUCAUGACUAAGGAACAUCUUAUAAAGGGACAUCAGUUUCUGUACUCUGACACUAAAUGGCCUCAAGUUGAUGGACUUCUUGUGACUCCUUUUUGCAGUUUUCAGAGCCCGCCCUUUUAUAUUUUUGAGACAGGGUCUCCUCUGUCACCCAGGCUGGAGUGCAGUGGUGCAGUCACAGCUCAUUGCAGCCUUGAUAUAUGUCCCAGGCUCAAGUGAUCAUCCAACUUCAGCCUCCAGAGUAGCUGGGACUACAGGCACACACCAGCACACCCUGUUAAUUUUUUUUUUGUUAUUUGUAGAGACAGGAUCUCCCUAUGUUGCUCAGGCUGGUCUUGAACUCCUGGGCUCAAGCAGUCCUCUGGCCUUGGCCUCAAAGUGUUGUGUGAGGCACUUCACCUGGCCCCUUUCUUUUAAUUGGGCUCUCUCUUCUCACACCCUAAUGCCACUUGUUGCAGUGGUGCACCUGUCUUGAAUCUUGUCUACCUUUUCCUCUAAUUUGAUGCUGCCUUUUGGCAAUGAGCUGGAAGUUCCAGAUAUCCAGAAUUGGGUCUUACUGAGUUAGGGCUCAGAAUGUGCUCUGAUUGAUUAGACUGCUUGGGCCUUUUGAUGCCUACUGUGGCUGCAGAUGUGCCUCUUUUGCUUAUUUCCCUCUUGGUUCUAAGUGGCAGUGAGUGGAGGACUGUGGAUGAGUGACCCCCCAAAAAGUAAGAUAUUGUCACAUAAGCUCUUGAGACAGUUAACUCAUUAUCUGCAGUUUCUUCCAUUCCACAAUAGGCUACUUAUUUUUAAUGCUGUAUUACAUUGAGAAUAUACUCAUGUAUAAUUUUUAUAAGAAAAAUAUUUAACUAUAUAUUUACAGAAGGUGACAUUUCAAAAGGCCCGGGAAUACUCUGUCAAGACCGCACGCUUGCCAAUCCAGGAAUACAUGGUCAGAAACCAGAAUGGGAAAAACUAUCAUUCAGAGAUACUGGCCAUCAAUCAAGGUACUUCUUACACGGCCCCCAUCCAGGGUGUGUGAGUUCUGGUGCUGCUGCUUUGCACUGUGUUUAAGUGGCCUUUGAGUCAGUCUCCUCUGUGACUAAUGUGUGUGGACUUUAUUGCAUGUACGUCAUGACAUAUAUUCUGGCCACUAAGAGGCAUUCUGUUUUCUUCGUCACCAACUAUGUUAAAGAUAGUUGAAAUUGUCCCCUUGGCCAGGUGCAGUGGCUCACACCUGUAAUCCUGUAAUCCACUUUCAGAGGCCGAGGUGGGUGGAUCACCUGAGGUUAGGAGUUCGAAACCAGCCUGGCCAACAUGGUGAAACCCCAUCUCUACUAAAAUACAAAAAUCAGUCAGGCGUGGUGGUGCACGCCUGUAAUACCAAUUAUUCCAGAGGCUGAGGCAUGAGAACCACUUGAACCUGGGAAGUGGAGGUUGCAGUGAGCCGAGAUCACACCACUGCACUCCAGCCUGGGUGACAGUGAUACUCUGUCUCAAAAACAAAAAAAAAAGCUGGGCACGGUGGCUCACACCUGUAAUCCCAGCACUUUGGGAGGCUGAGGUGGGCAGAUCACCUGAGGUCGGGAGGUCGAGACCAGCCUGACCAACAUGGAGAAACACCGUCUCUACUAAAAAUACAAAAAUUAGCAGGGCAUAGUGGCAGGCGCCUGUAAUCCCAGCUAAUCUGGAGGCUGAGGCAAGAGAAUUGCUUGAAUCUGGGAGGUGCAGGUUGCGGUGAGCUGAGAUCGUGCCAUUGCACUCCAGCCUGAGCAACAAGAGUGCAACUCCGCCUCAAAAAAAAAAAAAAAAAAAAAAAAAAAAAAAAAAAAAAUUGUCCCCUUCAUCUAGAAUGCCCAGCUUUUAACCUCUCACCACUGAAUUCCUGUUUGAUCUUCAGGGUUCAGUUCAGGAGCAUCUUGGCCCUUCCCCAUCCCAGGCCACAGCAGAGCCCUUCUGUUUCCCAUUUUACUGUGUUCCUUUCUGUUGCACCCUAUCCAUUCAUAGGCCUGUAUCUUUCAGGGUAGGCUGAGGUCCUUGAGAGCAAGCAGAGCCUGUGUCCUUGCCUCUCCCCGCAAGACCUUAGUACCACAUAUGGUGCAGAAUAGGUUUGUUGAACGAAAUAUUACAGAACAUCCUUUUCAUUUACUCGUUCUUUUUUUCCCUCUGUGGUCACUGUGUUUUCUGUUUACUCUCUAACAGUGUUUGAUAUCCUGUCCACUUACUUAGAGACUCACAACUGGCCUGAAGCAUUGAAGAAAGGAGUUUCUUCAGGAAAAGGCUAUAUUCUUCGGAACUCAGUGGAAUGAUGGGCCUAAGAUUGCAGCUGCGUGGCCAGGUGCUCACGCCGUAAUGCCAACACUUUGGUAGACCGAAGUGGGCAGAUCACCUGAGGUCAGGAGUUCACGACCAGCCUGGCCAACAUGGUGAAACCCUUCUCUACUGAAAAUACAAAAAUUAGCCAGGUGUGGUGGCGCAUACCUGUAGUCCCAGCUACUUGGGAGGCUGAGGCAGGAGAAUCACUUGAACUCGGGAGGCGAAGGUUGCAGUGAGCCGAGAUUUCACCAGUGCACUCCAGCCUGGGUGACAGAGCAAGACUCCAUCUCAAAAAAAAAAUAAAUAAAAAAAAAUGCAGCUGCAGGAGUGAGGCGCUUGGAGGUACCUUGACCCAAAGAGCAGGGCAGAGGGUGGCAGUGGCACAUAGGCAAGUGUCUUUGCAUGACAUCUUCUCAGAGCUUCACAAUAAUGUCAGGGACCACAUUUAAUGCUUUUUAAUCUCCCAUAGUGCCUGGCUCACAGGAAGUGCUCAGAUAUGUUAAGUAAUAAAAAGUUAAUGUGGUGGGUGCAGUGGCUCACGCCUGUAAUCCCAGCACUUUGGGAGGCUGAGGUGAGUGGAUUACAAGGUCAGGAGUUCCAGACCAGCCUGGCUAAUAUGGUGAAACCUCGUCUCUACUAAAAAUACAAAAAUUAGCUGGGCAUGGUGGUGCGUGCCUGUAGUCUCAGCUACUCAGGAGGCUGAGGCAGGAGAAUCGCCUGAACCCGGGCGGCGGAGGUUGUAGUGAGCCAAGAUCCAGCCUGGGCGACAGAGCCAGACUCUUGUCUCGAGGGGAAAAAAAAAAAAAAUUAUGUAACAAGGAAUUAGCCUCAAAACCACAUGGCUUUGGACGUGCUAAUUCAACUUUUGUACAUCUAUUUGUGAGAGACCUCUUGAAAUUGUUUAAAUGGUUACAUCAAGAGUUUAAUAUUCACUAAACUGGCAUCAUAAAAUUGUAUGACUUUCUCCA